AGAAGCCCCACGACGAUGGCGGCAAUGGCGGUGGCGCUGCGGGGAUUAGGAGGGCGCUUCCGGUGGCGGACGCAGGCCGUGGCGGGCGGGGUGCGGGGCGCGGCGCGGGGCGCAGCAGGUCAGCGGGACUAUGAUCUCCUGGUGGUCGGCGGGGGAUCUGGUGGCCUGGCUUGUGCCAAGGAGGCCGCCCAGCUGGGAAGGAAGGUGGCCGUGGUGGACUACGUGGAACCUUCUCCCCAAGGCACCCGGUGGGGCCUCGGCGGCACCUGCGUCAACGUGGGCUGCAUCCCCAAGAAGCUGAUGCACCAGGCGGCACUGCUGGGAGGCCUGAUCCAAGAUGCCCCCAACUAUGGCUGGGAGGUGGCCCAGCCCGUGCCGCAUGACUGGAGGAAGAUGGCAGAAGCUGUUCAAAAUCACGUGAAAUCCUUGAACUGGGGCCACCGUGUCCAGCUUCAGGACAGAAAAGUCAAGUACUUUAACAUCAAAGCCAGCUUUGUUGACGAGCACACGGUUUGCGGCGUUGCCAAAGGUGGGAAAGAGAUUCUGCUGUCAGCCGAUCACAUCAUCAUUGCUACUGGAGGGCGGCCGAGAUACCCCACGCACAUCGAAGGUGCCUUGGAAUAUGGAAUCACAAGUGAUGACAUCUUCUGGCUGAAGGAAUCCCCUGGAAAAACGUUGGUGGUCGGGGCCAGCUAUGUGGCCCUGGAGUGUGCUGGCUUCCUCACCGGGAUUGGGCUGGACACCACCAUCAUGAUGCGCAGCAUCCCCCUCCGCGGCUUCGACCAGCAAAUGUCCUCCAUGGUCAUAGAGCACAUGGCAUCUCAUGGCACCCGGUUCCUGAGGGGCUGUGCCCCCUCGCGGGUCAGGAGGCUCCCUGAUGGCCAGCUGCAGGUCACCUGGGAGGACAGCACCACCGGCAAGGAGGACACGGGCACCUUUGACACCGUCCUGUGGGCCAUAGGUCGAGUCCCAGACACCAGAAGUCUGAAUUUGGAGAAGGCUGGGGUAGAUACUAGCCCCGACACUCAGAAGAUCCUGGUGGACUCCCGGGAAGCCACCUCUGUGCCCCACAUCUACGCCAUUGGUGACGUGGUGGAGGGGCGGCCUGAGCUGACACCCAUAGCGAUCAUGGCCGGGAGGCUCCUGGUGCAGCGGCUCUUCGGCGGGUCCUCAGAUCUGAUGGACUACGACAAUGUUCCCACGACCGUCUUCACCCCGCUGGAGUAUGGCUGUGUGGGGCUGUCCGAGGAGGAGGCAGUGGCUCGCCACGGGCAGGAGCAUGUUGAGGUCUAUCACGCCCAUUAUAAACCACUGGAGUUCACGGUGGCUGGACGAGAUGCAUCCCAGUGUUAUGUAAAGAUGGUGUGCCUGAGGGAGCCCCCACAGCUGGUGCUGGGCCUGCAUUUCCUUGGCCCCAACGCAGGCGAAGUUACUCAAGGAUUUGCUCUGGGGAUCAAGUGUGGGGCUUCCUAUGCGCAGGUGAUGCGGACCGUGGGUAUCCAUCCCACAUGCUCUGAGGAGGUAGUCAAGCUGCGCAUCUCCAAGCGCUCAGGCCUGGACCCCACGGUGACAGGCUGCUGAGGGUAAGCGCCAUCCCUGCAGGCCAGGGCACACGGUGCGCCCGCCGCCAGCUCCUCGGAGGCCAGACCCAGGUAUGCAGGUGGGGCUGGCUCUGUUUGAGGACAGGGCAUGUGGCAGGGGUGCAGGAGCCCUGGCCAUGGGCUCCCUCCAGGUGUACAGCAAGGCUACACCUGCCACGCCACCCAGAAUGGGUGCUCCAUCCUGUAACCAGGCCACAGCGGUGACAGGCAGAAGGGGAAGUUCCCAGGGGCCCAAACCUCCCCGGGGGACCCCAGACCCCGGCCUGGCCACAGCUGCUCCCCACACACAGGAGGUAUCAAGAAACGGGGCUCAUCCUUAGCAGCCUAUCCCAGGUGGAUGUUGGCGUGGAAGGUGUCCCGGGUGGGCUAAAGUCGGGCAUCUCAAGUUGCUGCCCCACAGGGGGCUGCAGUCGGGAAGCUGGCCUCCCACCGAGGCCUCCCACCAAGGCCUGGCUCCUGCAGAGUUCAGCGCCCGCUCAUUUCCCUAUCUCCCAGAAGGUGGAGACGCUGCCCUGUGAUGGCCGGCCCUGCCCAGCCUGCCCUGCACAUCUGGUUCUGUUCCAGCUCUGCAGAGCCAGGCUGACCGGGGGGCAUGUUGUUCAUCGUGACCUCUUCUGGGGAGGAAGAAACUGGCAAGGGCUCCUGGCCUCUGCCCCAGGGAUGCCUGUGCCAGAGCCCCCUCGCCUCGUGGUCUAAUAGUGCAUCCUCCGGCCUGGGCUGCAGGGCAGGGGCCGGGGCAGGGUGGGCCCUCAGCCCGUGCCAUCCAGCCCACCUGGGGCACCCCCAUGGCUGUCAGCCCCUCCCAGGGUUGGGGUGUUUGGGCUCCAUCUCUCCCCCGGGGCUGAGGUGGAGACCAGGCAGAGCAGUGGGCUCCCCCCAAGAUGCCUGUGGACAGGCUCUAGGGUCUGCAUGGCGCCGAGGGGCUCUGGGGAGGCCUCUCUGGGGGUACUCAGGGCCCCCUGCUUCACCGUGGCCGCCUCCCCCCGGCGGGGCCGCGCUCGAUAGGGAUAAACAAAGGGCAUCCUGAGGAAACUCUUAUCAGAACAUUACACCUCCCAGAGCUGUUUUGUUAGGAGCCUGCUAUAAAUUUUUAUCAUUUCAAAAUAUUUUUGUAGCACCGCGUCGCUCCCUGUGACGCAUCGCCCUGGGGUGGGGCCAUUCUCUGCUGGGUUUAUUUCUCACCCAUCUCCCUUGGGGGUCCCUGGGUGUGGCAGUGGGAGACAUAGCUAGGCUGAUGUGAGGGGUGGGUGGCUGACCUGUGCUGACCUUCCUGUUGUUGGCAGGAUGGCUGCAGGCCAGGUUUGGGGGGCCUCAACCCUCUCCUGGAGCGCCUGUGAGAUGGUCAGCGUGGAGCGCAAGUGCUGGACAGGUGGCCCGUGUGCCCCACAGGGAUGGCUCAGGGGACUGUCCACCUCACCCCUGCACCUCUCAGCCUCUGCCGCCGGGCACCCCCCCCCAGGCUCCUGGUGCCAGAUGAUGACGACCUGGGUGGAAACCUACCCUGUGGGCACCCAUGUCCGAGCCCCCUGGCAUUUCUGCAAUGCAAAUAAAGAGGGUACUUUUUCUGAA